AAGAGCAAAGUCAGCGGUGCCUACAGUCAGCACCAUGCUGGGCCUGCCGUGGAAGGGAGGUCUGUCCUGGGCGCUGCUGCUGCUUCUCUUAGGCUCCCAGAUCCUGCUGAUCUAUGCCUGGCAUUUCCACGAGCAAAGGGACUGUGAUGAACACAAUGUCAUGGCUCGUUACCUCCCUGCCACAGUGGAGUUUGCUGUCCACACAUUCAACCAACAGAGCAAGGACUACUAUGCCUACAGACUGGGGCACAUCUUGAAUUCCUGGAAGGAGCAGGUGGAGUCCAAGACUGUAUUCUCAAUGGAGCUACUGCUGGGGAGAACUAGGUGUGGGAAAUUUGAAGACGACAUUGACAACUGCCAUUUCCAAGAAAGCACAGAGCUGAACAAUACUUUCACCUGCUUCUUCACCAUCAGCACCAGGCCCUGGAUGACUCAGUUCAGCCUCCUGAACAAGACCUGCUUGGAGGGAUUCCACUGAGUGAAACCCACUCACAGGCUUGUCCAUGUGCUGCUCCCACAUUCCGUGGACAUCAGCACUACUCUCCUGAGGACUCUUCAGUGGCUGAGCAGCUUUGGACUUGUUUGUUAUCCUAUUUUGCAUGUGUUUGAGAUCUCAGAUCAGUGUUUUAGAAAAUCCACACAUCUUGAGCCUAAUCAUGUAGUGUAGAUCAUUAAACAUCAGCAUUUUAAGAAA